GAGACACAGCCGGAAAGGCUGGCAGGCAGGAGGGCUGGGGCGAGCACUGGGGGGCCAUGGAGCGGGCAGAAGAGCCCGUGGUCUAUCAGAAGCUGCUGCCCUGGGAGCCAAGCUUGGAGUCGGAGGAGGAAGUGGAGGAGGAGGAGACAUCAGAGGCGCUGGUUCUAAACCCCCGGAGGCACCAGGACUCUUCCAGGAACAAGGCUGGCGGGCUGCCCGGAACCUGGGCCCGUGUAGUGGCAGCCCUGCUGCUGCUGGCUGUUGGCUGCUCCCUGGCUGUGAGGCAGCUCCAGAAUCAGGGCAGGUCGACAGGAAGCUUGGGCUCUGUGGCCCCUCCACCCGGCGGACACUCCCACGGCCCUGGCGUAUACCACCACGGUGCCAUCAUCAGCCCUGCAGCCACAUGCUCCCACCUAGGCCGAGAGCUGCUUGUUGCCGGGGGCAACGUCGUGGAUGCUGGAGUUGGAGCUGCAUUGUGCCUGGCAGUGGUGCAUCCUCAUGCCACGGGGCUAGGUGCCAUGUUUUGGGGCCUCUUCCACGAUAGCUCCUCAGGCAAUUCCACGGCCCUGACAUCAGGCCCAGCACAGACCCUGGCCCCCGGCCUGGGGCUGCCCGCGGCUCUGCCCACCCUGCACCUGCUGCAUGCACGCUUCGGCCGCCUGCCCUGGCCACGCCUGCUAGUGGGCCCCACCACGCUGGCUCAGGAGGGCUUCCUGGUGGACACACCCCUGGCAAGGGCUCUGGUGGCUCGGGGCACAGAAGGCCUCUGUCCACUACUUUGCCAUGCUGAUGGGACACCCCUGGGCGCUGGGGCCCGAGCCACCAACCCACAACUGGCAGCUGUGCUUCGCAGCGCAGCCCUCGCUCCCACCUCAGACCUUGCUGGGGAUGCUCUACUGAGUCUACUGGCGGGAGACCUGGGGGUGGAGGUGCCCUCGGCUGUGCCCAGGCCCACUUUGGAACCAGCAGAGCAGCUACCUGUGCCCCAGGGCAUCCUGUUCACCACCCCCAGUCCCUCAGCUGGCCCAGAACUGCUGGCACUGUUGGAGGCAGCCCUGCGCUCCGGGGCGCCCAUCCCUGACCCCUGCCCACCGUUCCUGCAGACUGCUGUGAGCCCCGAGAGCAGUGCCCUGGCCGCCGUGGACAGCAGCGGCUCUGUGCUCCUUCUCACCUCCUCGCUCAACUGCUCCUUUGGCUCUGCACACCUGUCCCCAAGCACUGGGGUUCUGCUCAGCAACCUGGUGGCCAAGUCUACCACUAGUGCCUGGGCCUGCCCCCUCAUCCUCCGUGGCAGCCUGGAUGACACAGAGGCUGAUGUGUUGGGGCUUGUGGCUUCAGGGACCCCUGAUGUGGCCAGGGCCAUGACUCACACCCUACUCAGGCAUCUGGCAGCAAGGCCCCCUACCCAGGCCCAGCACCAGCAUCAGGGUCAGCAAGAACCAACAGAGCAUCCCAGCACUUGUGGCCAAGGGACCCUGCUCCAGGUGGCAGCCCACACAGAGCACGCCCAUGUCUCCAGUGUCCCCCAUGCCUGCUGCCCCUUCCAGGGGUUCUAACAGGAUGGGGGUGGGUCUGGCAGAAGGCAGAGUUAUCUGAAGCAUGGGGGCAGGAGCAGAGCAGACACAGCAGCAAUGGAGUGUGCACCCGCAGGGUGUGGUGCCUCACACCUGUAAUCUCAGCACUUUGGGUGGUCAAGGCAGGAAGAUACCUCGAGGCCAGGAGUUUGAAACUAGCCUAGACAACAAAGCAAGAUCUCAUCUGUACUAAAAAUUUAAAAAUUUGCCAGGGGCGGUGGCACAUGCCUGUUGUCCCAGCUGCUUGGGAGGCUGAGGCAGGAAGCUCGCUUGAGCUCAGGAGUUCAAGGCUGCAGAGAGCUAGGAUCACACCACUGCACUCCAGCCUGGACAACAGACUUUUGAAGCAACUGGAGUCAGGGCUUCCCUGAUGGGCAGCACAGGUGACCAACAACCAGAGAGGGGAGAGCCUGGGUUGGUAUCUUUCAGCUUCCCCCUGCUCCGCUCACCUCCUGCCUCCUGGGGCACCAGAUGUGCAAGGUGAAUGUUUUCAUUUCACUUUCUAGAACAGACAGCAAAGCAGGGAAGCGGCUGAGAGGGUGAGAAGGCGCCCCAGGGGCUUGGGUACAAAGGGGUUGGAGUUGAGCGUGUGGAAAUUCAAGGCGAAGGUUAGCCCUGACCUCCCCCAAGGGUUAGGUCCUCUCUGGACCACAGCCCUCUAUAAACAGCUUCUCAAACCAAGAAGCGAGGGUGACCAGUAGCAGUUCCCCUCCCCUGCCAUUGUAAAAGGCUUCUCUGAUUUAAUAGACCGUUUGAUCCCACCACCUUUACCUCCCACUCCCAAGAAAAUUCUUCUCCGUAAUGGCACCACAAUGUACCCAGUUAUUUCAGUCUCAAACCUGGCAUCCCCCUCAUUUCCUCUCCCCCGACAUCUAACUCCAUCACCCACCCCACCUGCUCCACAUCAGCCCAAAUCUGACCUGUUCUCAUUUUCCCUGGGUCCAGUCCACCACUAUCUCUAAAUGGUCUUCCCGUGCUUCCACCUGCGCAGACCUACAGUCCAUCCCCCACACAGCAGCCAGCAUCAUCUUGUUAAAAUGUAAAUCGGAUCCAGGCUUGCCCCUGCAUUAAACUCACCAGUGACUUCCCA